UUAUGCUAUUUUUCCUGACUGUGGCCUCACUUUCUUCCCAAUAAAUGUUUCAAUCUGUUGAUACUAAUGUUUUUUCUCAUGAUACUUGUAAGAUAACUGAUUUUAACAAAAGGUGGCACACCUAUUAAAGACAUGGUUAAGUUUCAUUGGCUGUAUAGCAUCUCUAAUUGGAAGACUACAUGGCAUCUAUCCAGGUUGGAGUUGUAAUCACCUAGGGAUGUCUACAUCUGUCUACCUAGAUCAGUCUGUCAGUUCCAUCGAGGUCUGUAUUUCAAAGUCCAUACAUAACACACGGUUCUUCCCAUUUUACAGAAUUAUUUUUUCAAACCAAAGUUCACAUACUGCUGGUGGGAACAGGUUCAAAUAGGGAAUGCUGAUACAUAUCAACAACCUUUGAGACAAACCUGUUCACACAGUGAGUGUGGAGCCCUUGGCCCCCCUACUUUCUCUCUCGCAGGCCCCGACAUCACCCUGGGCUUGCGCUGUUGGUAGUGUUCAAAGGAAAACUUUAGAAACAUUAAAUUUUACAGAGUUUAAUUGAGCAAAGAAUGAUUCAGGAAUCAGGGAACCCCUCAAACCAGAAUAGGCUCAGAGAGACUCCAGUGCCACUGUGUGGCCAAAGACUUACGGACAGAAAAGGGAGUGAGGCACAGAAGGCAGAGGUGAGGCCUGCAAACAGCAGGGUGGCUACAGCUCGUGUCUGGCUUAUUGAAACAGAGUUUGAAGUGCUGCUGCCUGUGACUGAUUCAAGAGUAGGUUACAGUGUCCACACAUCCAAUUAGAUGACUGUUCACUACGUAUGGAGAAACCUAUAGGCUAAACUUACAGUAUGUAAGGAGGCGGCUUCAGGCUACAGCUGAGUAGUGUGUCCUUACAGUUGGAACCAGGAGUUCAUGGGAAUUCUUCAUCAUCCAGUGGUCUGUAAAUGUUGCCCAUGCUGAGUAGUCUGUCCUUACAGUGUGAACCAGGGGUUCAUGGGAAUUCUUCACCAUCCAGUAGUCUGUAAAUGUUGCCCAUGCUGAGUAGUGUGUCCUUACAGUGUGAACCAGGGGUUCAUGGGAAUUCUUCACCAUCCAGUGGUCUGUAAAUGUUGCCCAUGCUUUAGUUUUGUUACCUGGUUGCUCUGUUUUUAUGGGAUUGUGAGAAACUGAAAAACUGUGACUGCUGGAGCCAUUUUCCCACAAUCCCCAUUUUUUAAAAAUCCCAUAAAGGCUCUCUCGUGAGCACCGCACGUUUUCCCUUGUAGUCACGAGGGUAGGGGCUGGAGAAAGCAGCAGAGAUAGUCAAAAACCCACAGCUACAAAAAAUGCACUCCUAAGAGCAAGUAAUGGCGAGGGCUAAAAGGCACUGUGCCCCUUCUGGGCCAUUCUAAUUACCACAUUUAAAUGGUUUUGAGAAAAGAGAAUUUUUAUCUGAGGAACGCGAGUUCUUUUAAUUAUCAGGCCGAGAGAGACAUUCAAAUGAGGCGACAAUCGCGCCCUACUACCCCUUGACCUGUGUUCACCUCUUUAAACUGCUACUGGUGGCAACAGCGCCACAAACAGCUAUAAAUUAACCUAAUGACGCCACAAUGGACACUAUACCCACACUCAAUAGCUGAACAACAUAUAGUCAGUCACUAAUCAAUGUUAUUUCUGUAAACCAGUGAGAAUUCCUCACAAACAAGUUCCUAUUAGUCCACUCCCUGGCCCCCUUUUUUGCCUUUAAAAUCCACUGUUAACUGCUAAUCGGAGUACACAUUCAGGGCGCCUUGAAUUUGUGCUCAAGUGUGGCCCAAAUAAACUCUCUACUUAGAGAAACUGUGUCUCCGCUCGUUUUCAGGCCGACAGUUUCCAAAAUGUUAGUAUUCAGCCUAACAUGAGAAAAGUCACCAUAUAAAAGUGAGGGGGGAAAAGCAAAUACAGGAUAAUCUCAAUUGUAUAUAAAAUUUAUAUACGUAAGGACAAAGAUACAUAGUAAAAAAAAAAUUCUGGCAGGUAUUAAGGCUGAAAAAAUUAAAACAGUCCAGAGCGGUCUGGCUCAGGCCAGCCUGGGCCUGCCGAGUAGCUGGGACCUCAGCCACCGCGCCUGGCUAAGUAUUAAUGAAUCUGUUUUAGAGAUAGGGUCUUGCUACGUUGCGCAGGCUGGUCUCCAACUCCCAGGCUCAGGUGAUCCGCCCGCCACAGCCUCCCGAAGUGCUGAGCCUCCCAAAGUGCUGAGACUACAGGCCUGGCCGCCCGCCCGCCAGCUUAAUUCACGUAAAUUCCAGACAAACGUAGAAAGUGGCUCCUUUAGUAAGCCACUUGCGGCUGCUGCUCAUCAGGGUUCGCCUGGGGCCACUGAGACCACGCGCCGGUGCCCGCCCUCCCGCUGCGGUCCGAUUUUCUGAACCAACCAGGCGCUUCCGGGCGCCUUGCCCCAGACGGGCCCACCGCCUGCGCGGGCCGAGGGCGGCGCACCUGCCCCUGCGCUUCCGCAUCGAAGAGCGGUUCUGGUGAGGUUGGAAGGAUGCAGCCACCCGGUUGUCAUGAAAGGCCUGUGUGCUGAAUGUGGCCAAGACCUCACCCAGUUGCAGAGUAAGAACGGGAAGCAGCAGGUGCCGCUGUCCACGGCGACCGUGUCCAUGGUGCACAGCGUGCCGGAGUUGAUGGUGAGCUCCGAGCAAGCUGAACAGCUGGGAAGAGAAGACCAGCAGCGACUGCACCGAAACCGGAAGCUGGUGCUCAUGGUGGACUUGGACCAGACGUUGAUUCACACAACCGAGCAGCACUGUCAGCAGAUGUCGAAUAAAGGCAUCUUUCACUUCCAGCUGGGCCGGGGUGAGCCCAUGCUGCACACGCGCCUGCGUCCACACUGCAAGGACUUCCUGGAGAAGAUCGCCAAGCUGUACGAGCUGCACGUCUUCACCUUCGGCAGCCGGCUGUACGCACACACCAUCGCAGGCUUUUUAGACCCCGAGAAGAAGCUUUUUUCUCACCGAAUAUUAUCAAGGGAUGAAUGUAUUGACCCAUUUUCUAAAACGGGAAACCUUAGAAAUCUCUUUCCUUGUGGAGACUCAAUGGUUUGCAUUAUUGAUGAUCGAGAAGAUGUCUGGAAGUUUGCCCCCAAUCUGAUAACUGUGAAGAAAUAUGUAUACUUCCAGGGCACGGGUGAUAUGAAUGCGCCCCCUGGGUCCCGAGAAUCUCAGACGAGAAAGAAAGUAAAUCAUUCUCGAGGCACUGAGGUCUCAGAGCCAUCUCCGCCCGUGAGAGACCCUGAGGGGGUAACGCAGGCCCCUGGAGUGGAGCCCAGCAAUGGCCUGGAGAAGCCUGCACGGGAGCUGAACGGCAGCGAGGCCGCCACCCCGCGGGACUCACCCCGCCCCGGGAAGCCAGACGAGAGGGACAUCUGGCCCCCUGCCCAGGCCCCCACCAGCAGCCAAGAGCUGGCAGGCGCUCCUGAGCCCCAGGGAUCCUGUGCGCAGGGUGGCCGGGUGGCACCGGGACAGCGGCCUGCCCAGGGUGCCACGGGCACUGACCUGGACUUUGACUUAUCCAGCGACAGCGAGAGCAGCAGUGAGUCCGAGGGCACGAAGUCCUCCUCCUCCGCCUCUGAUGGCGAAAGCGAGGGGAAAAGAGGCCGGCAGAAGCCGAAGGCUGCCCCAGAGGGAGCCGGGGCGCUGGCACAGGGCAGUUCCCUGGAGCCGGGGCGGCCUGCAGCACCGAGUCUCCCCGGAGAGGCCGAGCCUGGCGCGCAUGCCCCGGACAAGGAGCCUGAGCUGGGUGGGCAGGAGGAGGGCGAGCGGGAUGGCCUCUGCGGCCUGGGCAACGGCUGUGCCGACAGGAAGGAGGCGGAGACCGAGUCACAGAACAGCGAGCUGUCGGGGGUCACUGCGGGUGAGUCCCUGGACCAGAGCAUGGAGGAGGAGGAGGAGGAGGACACGGAUGAGGAUGACCACCUCAUCUACCUGGAGGAGAUCCUGGUCCGUGUACACACUGACUACUAUGCCAAGUAUGACCGCUACCUCAACAAGGAGAUCGAGGAGGCGCCGGACAUCCGCAAGAUCGUGCCGGAGCUCAAGAGCAAGGUGCUGGCAGACGUGGCCAUAAUUUUCAGUGGGCUACACCCGACAAACUUCCCGAUAGAGAAGACGCGGGAGCAUUACCACGCCACGGCGCUGGGAGCGAAGAUCCUCACUCGGCUGGUGCUGAGCCCCGACGCCCCUGACAGGGCCACGCACCUGAUCGCCGCGCGAGCUGGCACAGAGAAGGUGCUGCAGGCACAGGAGUGCGGACACCUGCACGUGGUCAACCCUGACUGGCUGUGGAGCUGCCUGGAGCGCUGGGACAAGGUGGAGGAGCAGCUCUUCCCGCUCAGGGACGAUCACACCAAGGCACAGAGGGAGAACAGCCCUGCGGCCUUUCCCGACCGGGAGGGUGUGCCCCCCACCGCCUUGUUCCACCCGAUGCCGGUUCUUCCCAAGGCCCAGCCUGGCCCCGAGGUUCGGAUCUACGACUCCAACACGGGGAAGCUCAUCAGGACGGGCGCCCGGGGGCCCCCAGCACCCUCCAGCUCCCUACCCAUCCGCCAGGAGCCCUCUUCCUUCAGAGCGGUUCCGCCACCCCAGCCGCAGAUGUUUGGUGAAGAGCUGCCUGACGCUCAGGACGGAGAGCAGCCUGGCCCUUCUAGAAGAAAGCGACAGCCCAGUAUGUCUGAGACAAUGCCGCUGUACACUCUUUGUAAGGAGGAUUUAGAGAGUAUGGACAAAGAGGUGGACGACAUCCUUGGAGAAGGCAGCGACGACAGCGACAGCGAGAAGAGGAGGCCUGAGGAGCAGGAGGAGGAGCCCCAGCCCCGGAAGCCAGGGACCCGCAGGGAGCGGACGCUCGGGGCACCUGCGUCCAGCGAGAGGAGCGCGGCAGGGGGCCGGGGGCCCAGAGGCCACAAGAGGAAGCUGAAUGAAGAGGACGCCGCCAGCGAGUCCAGCAGGGAGUCCAGCAACGAGGAUGAGGGCAGCAGCUCCGAGGCCGACGAGAUGGCCAAGGCGCUGGAGGCGGAGCUCAACGACCUCAUGUGAGCGCGGGCAGCGGGCAGGGACUGAAGCCUGACCGACCUCCAGCAGCACUCGGACGUCCCCGGACCAGCCCUCAGUCUCGGUCCACGCUGCUUUCUUCCCAAAGGACAUGUAUAUUUGCAGAGCUCCACAUACAGAAACACAUUAUUUUGCAGAAAUAGGUGUUUUUAAGAAGUUUUACUACAGGAAUGUCUACUUUUGUAAGUGACAGGUGUUAAAGGCCCAGGUGUGCUGUGCCAAAGAGCUCAGCAGAGGCUCACGUGGCCCAGGCUGGUGCGCCCGCUGUCUCGGUAAGGGGCGGGUUGGUGUGUUUUCCCCUUGUGUACCAGAGCACAUUCCUUAGGGGACGGCUUUGGGGGUCCCACGAGACAUGGACUAGGAGUUUAAGCAGGACAGUGUGCGUGCACGAGCUCCGAGCCCAGCACAGACAUGCCUGGAACCCCCGCCGCCUGCUGCUCCCUCCUAGGGAACCCAUUUCCGGGGAACGCCGUGACUGUCGGGCAGCCUGGAGCUUCCUGCAGCCUCCUACGCAGGGUCCACGCCACGUGGCCUGGGCUGCCAUCCUGCCGUCCUCCCACUGGCAUCCUGGCAAGGGGGCGUUGCUUUUCCUGGGCGGCCUUUUAUGUCUUGGAGACACCUGAUGUAAAGUUUCUGUAAAUCUAUUUCAUAUCUGACCCACCAAACAGAUUUCUCUUUAAUAAAAAUCCUUUUUGUAAGUUCUCUUCUCGUGGGUGUGUGGCAGCGGUGAGCACCCGCCUCCUCCCUCGCUGGGAUCCAGCUCCUUAGCUGUGAAACAGAAACGAAAAAAUUCCCACGGACAGGACCGUGUGGAACGGCAGAAAUGGAAACCGCAGAACUGCGAGCGUGAUGAUCUCAGGGUUUCGCCUCUGAGCAUAAGAACCAGGCUUGUAGCUGGUAUUUUAAAACGGUUAAGUGUGAAGAAUUACUCUCUUGCAUUAUUUUCAUCCUUCCCUUUUGUUUGUUUGGGAUGCGGGGGCCCGAGAGCUACAGGUAGGUGCUGGGCUAUGGCCGCCGCCAGGACCCCUCCCGGCCAGCAGCCUCGGCUCACGUCCCCUCCUCCUCCCAGCAUCAGUCCCGCAGCGUGGCGGUGGGAGGCUGCACCUCGAGGCCACGGCCCUUCUCCAAAAGCACACACUCCUGCUUUCCGACGGCACCCUCCCCUGACCACAGCUCGGGAGGUGGCACGUGUGAGAACUCUCCAUCCACAGGAUGUGGCUCUCGCGGGACCUCCAGGCUCAGGCUGUCUCCGCUGGGUGUGGGACCUUUCCUGUGGGGUUUUCGAUGGAGGUUGGCUGGGGAGGGAGGCAUCCUCAGUGGGUAGAGGACCCCAGGGUCCUGGUGCUGCUGUCGUCAAGAUGCGGCGACAUGGUGGCAGAGGAAAGGCACCGUUACCCAGCAGCACGCCAGCCCCGGGUGACUGUUUCCUGUACUAACUAGGUUAUUUGCAGCGCCGAGUGAAGAGGCAGCUUCACCACCCAACCCACCUGUGGGUUCUCCGGGGUCUGCAGUCUGAGGAGGCUGCAGGAUGACCAGACGCCGGUCAGGGAGUUCCUCCUGUCCAGAGAAGCAGGAGGUGAACUGGGCCCACCUCAGGUCCGAUUUCGCCACGAGCAAGAAUGUAAGAUGAAUUGGACAGAAAACAAAAAUAGAUGUACAAGUUGAUACCCAAAGAAAGCAGAAGAUUCUACAGUUUAUAGGGAGGGGCACAAAACGUGCAGGGAGUAAUGUGCCGGGGGGUGGGGGCAGGGGCCGAUGAACGAGGCCUUGAUGCUGUGUGGAGACCUCUGGGAAAGGCUGGGAGACCUUCCCUCCUUCCACAGUGGUUUCUCCCUGAAGGCGAUUCUGCGUGUGGUUGGUCCUGCUGGGACCAAGGUGGCCCCUUGUUCUGCUCUUGGCCGAGUCCCCUCUGGCUUCAUGGGGGUGUUAAUGAGGCUCUGCAAGGCCUCCUUAAACACAGUGUGGAAAUACAGGUGGUGCUGCAGGGGCAGCGAGAACGGGGACCUCUGCUGCUGGGUCUGGCCUAGGGGUGAAGAGGACGGGAGGAGGGUGGCGUGGUAGCUGGCUGCGCGGGGCCUGGUGACGGGAGGGGCCGGACCGCAUGCAGCAUUCAGGACCAGCGUGGCCCUGGGUGUUCGCCUGUUCUGACCGUGUGGUCGAGUGAACAGAGCAUGCAGGGGAGAUGCAGCAGGUUCUCCCCGACGCGGAAGAGCAAGGGGUCCCCGGUUCCUGGAGGAGCAGCGGGAUUGCCCCAGGCUCUGGGAUCGCCCACGGGGGCAGCGGGCCAGCACCCCCAGCCGCAUCUCUGCACAGCCGUGCUGCACACCUUCUCCGUCACGUGUUGGAGGUGGGUCUCAGCACCAGCACAUCCACAUUGAUAGCUUAAAAUGGGACUUUUCUCCCGCCUGUCUCACUGUUGGCCCGCCCCCAUGCAGCGGUGGGGACCCCACUGCAGGGACUCCAAGAGCCCCAUCCUGUCCUCGGCUCCAGCCUCCAUCAGCACCAGCCGUGUCCUUGCAGCCCUGACUGGAGCAACUCCCAAACUCUGCUGCCCGGCAGGUCUUCUGACCCUGCCCGCGGUGAUGGCACCCUCUGGAAGGCUGGCCCAGGACGGCACCUCCAUGCUGGCAGCCCCUGAGUGUAGUGUGUGUUCUACACAAAAGAGCCAGGAAGUCAUCUGUGAUCAUUGUUUAAGGGACUGUGAUUAACGUUUAUGAAAUGUUCUGUGCUAUGCGAAGAAACCACUGAAUGUUAGGGAAAAUAUUAAAUACUGAAUAAUUAUACAACUGUUCCAAAUAAAGUCUUAAGAAGAAACUUGAA